GGAAACAAAACAGCGGCUGGUCUGGAAGGAACCUGAGCUACGAGCCGCGGCGGCAGCGGGGCGGCGGGGAAGCGUAUGUGCGUGAUGGGGAGUCCGGGCAAGCCAGGAAGGCACCGCGGACAUGGGCGGCCGCGGGCAGGGCCCGGCCCUUUGUGGCCGCCCGGGCCGCGAAGCCGGUGUCCUAAAAGAUGAGGGGCGGGGCGCGGCCGGUUGGGGCUGGGGAACCCCGUGUGGGAAACCAGGAGGGGCGGCCCGUUUCUCGGGCUUCGGGCGCGGCCGGGUGGAGAGAGAUUCCGGGGAGCCUUGGUCCGGAAAUGCUGUUUGCUCGAAGACGUCUCAGGGCGCAGGUGCCUUGGGCCGGGAUUAGUAGCCGUCUGAACUGGAGUGGAGUAGGAGAAAGAGGAAGCGUCUUGGGCUGGGUCUGCUUGAGCAACUGGUGAAACUCCGCGCCUCACGCCCCGGGUGUGUCCUUGUCCAGGGGCGACGAGCAUUCUGGGCGAAGUCCGCACGCCUCUUGUUCGAGGCGGAAGACGGGGUCUGAUGCUUUCUCCUUGGUCGGGACUGUCUCGAGGCAUGCAUGUCCAGUGACUCUUGUGUUUGCUGCUGCUUCCCUCUCAGAUUCUUCUCACCGUUGUGGUCAGCUCUGCUUUAGGCAUAUUAAUCCAUAGUGGAGGCUGGGAUGGGUGAGAGAAUUGAGGUGACUUUUCCAUAAUUCAGGUGAGAUGUGAUUAGAGUUCGAUCUGCGGUGGUGGCAGAGGCUUACAAGAAACACUAACGGGACAUGGGAACCAAUUGAGGAUCAGGGAAUAAAGUGUGAAGUUGACUAGGAGGUUUUCAGUUUAGAACAUGGCAGAGACAUUCUCAGAAAUAAGGAAGUUAGGAAGAAAGACCUGGUUUAGAGAGGAGGGCGAGGAAGUGGUUUGGAAGUGUCACUUUGGAAGUGCCAGCAGGUGAAAAUGCCCUGUGAACAGGACUGGAGCUGAAAACAGGAAUCAAUUCCAUAGAUUUCCAGUUGAUGUUGGAGCAGUGGAGAAGUCUAAGCUAAGGAAGGGGAAGAGGAGGCCAAGGCAAACACUUAGGAACACUUGCAACGAGGGGGUGGAAGAAGAGCAAGGAGCCAGCUGAGGAGAAUGAGUGUGGUUGGAGAACCACCACAGCGCAGGGUCGCCAGAGCUGAGGAAGGGGAGGGAAGCUUCAGGAAGGAAAAGGUUGGCAGGGAUUUUGAGUGUUAGGCCUGGUGUAGCAGAAGGAACAGAAGAUUUAGAGCAGCGCUAGCCAAUAGAAAUAAAAUGUGAGGCCCGGGGCGGUGGCUCACGCCUGUAAUCCCAGCACUUUGGGAGGCCGCGGGGCGGAUCCUUGAGCUGAGGAGUUCGAGACCAGACAACACGGCGAAACCCCGGCUCUACAAAAAAUUAGCUGGGCGUGGGGGCGCGCGCCUGUAGUCCCAGCUGCUCCCAAGCGAGGCUGAGGCAGGAGAAUCACUUGAACCCGGGAGAAGGAGGUUGCAGUAAGCCAAGAUUAUGCCACUGCACUGCAGCCUGGGCAAAAGAGUGAGACUGUCUCAAAAAAAAAAAAAACCUGUUUUGUUUUUCUUUUGGAGAAAAGGCAUACAAAUUUAUUAGCAUGCAGACUGGGAGAACCACAAGACCUAAUCUGGGAGCCUGCAAGUGACAACAGCCUUUGCGGUCCUUAGACAGCUUGGCCUGGAGGAGAACACAUGAAAGAAAGAACCUCAAGAGGCUUUGUUUUCUGUGAAACAGUAUUUCUAUACAGUUGCUCCAAUGACAGAGUUACCUGCACCGUUGUCCUACUUCCAGAAUGCACAGAUGUCUGAGGACAACCACCUGAGCAAUACUGUACGUAGCCAGAAUGACAAUAGAGAACGGCAGGAGCACAACGACAGACGGAGCCUUGGCCACCCUGAGCCAUUAUCUAAUGGACGACCCCAGGGUAACUCCCGGCAGGUGGUGGAGCAAGAUGAGGAAGAAGAUGAGGAGCUGACAUUGAAAUAUGGCGCCAAGCAUGUGAUCAUGCUCUUUGUCCCUGUGACUCUCUGCAUGGUGGUGGUCGUGGCUACCAUUAAGUCAGUCAGCUUUUAUACCCGGAAGGAUGGGCAGCUAAUCUAUACCCCAUUCACAGAAGAUACCGAGACUGUGGGCCAGAGAGCCCUGCACUCAAUUCUGAAUGCUGCCAUCAUGAUCAGUGUCAUUGUUGUCAUGACUAUCCUCCUGGUGGUUCUGUAUAAAUACAGGUGCUAUAAGGUCAUCCAUGCCUGGCUUAUUAUAUCAUCUCUAUUGUUGCUGUUCUUUUUUUCAUUCAUUUACUUGGGGGAAGUGUUUAAAACCUAUAACGUUGCUGUGGACUACAUUACUGUUGCACUCCUGAUCUGGAAUUUUGGUGUGGUGGGAAUGAUUUCCAUUCACUGGAAAGGUCCACUUCGACUCCAGCAGGCAUAUCUCAUUAUGAUUAGUGCCCUCAUGGCCCUGGUGUUUAUCAAGUACCUCCCUGAAUGGACUGCGUGGCUCAUCUUGGCUGUGAUUUCAGUAUAUGAUUUAGUGGCUGUUUUGUGUCCGAAAGGUCCACUUCGUAUGCUGGUUGAAACAGCUCAGGAGAGAAAUGAAACGCUUUUUCCAGCUCUCAUUUACUCCUCAACAAUGGUGUGGUUGGUGAAUAUGGCAGAAGGAGACCCGGAAGCUCAAAGGAGAGUAUCCAAAAAUUCCAAGUAUAAUGCAGAAAGCACAGAAAGGGAGUCACAAGACACUGUUGCAGAGAAUGAUGAUGGCGGGUUCAGUGAGGAAUGGGAAGCCCAGAGGGACAGUCAUCUAGGGCCUCAUCGCUCUACACCUGAGUCACGAGCUGCUGUCCAGGAACUUUCCAGCAGUAUCCUCGCUGGUGAAGACCCAGAGGAAAGGGGAGUAAAACUUGGAUUGGGAGAUUUCAUUUUCUACAGUGUUCUGGUUGGUAAAGCCUCAGCAACAGCCAGUGGAGACUGGAACACAACCAUAGCCUGUUUCGUAGCCAUAUUAAUUGGUUUGUGCCUUACAUUAUUACUCCUUGCCAUUUUCAAGAAAGCAUUGCCAGCUCUUCCAAUCUCCAUCACCUUUGGGCUUGUUUUCUACUUUGCCACAGAUUAUCUUGUACAGCCUUUUAUGGACCAAUUAGCAUUCCAUCAAUUUUAUAUCUAGCAUAUUUGCGGUUAGAAUCCCAUGGAUGUUUCUUCUUUGACUAUAACAAAAUCUGGGGAGGACAAAGGUGAUUUUCCUGUGUCCACAUCUAACAAAGUCAAGAUUCCCGGCUGGACUUUUGCAGCUUCCUUCCAAGUCUUCCUGACCACCUUGCACUAUUGGACUUUGGAAGGAGGUGCCUAUAGAAAACGAUUUUGAACAUACUUCAUCGCAGUGGACUGUGUCCCUCGGUGCAGAAACUACCAGAUUUGAGGGACGAGGUCAAGGAGAUAUGAUAGGCCCGGAAGUUGCUGUGCCCCAUCAGCAGCUUGACGCGUGGUCACAGGACGAUUUCACUGACACUGCGAACUCUCAGGACUACCGUUACCAAGAGGUUAGGUGAAGUGGUUUAAACCAAACGGAACUCUUCAUCUUAAACUACACGUUGAAAAUCAACCCAAUAAUUCUGUAUUAACUGAAUUCUGAACUUUUCAGGAGGUACUGUGAGGAAGAGCAGGCACCAGCAGCAGAAUGGGGAAUGGAGAGGUGGGCAGGGGUUCCAGCUUCCCUUUGAUUUUUUGCUGCAGACUCAUCCUUUUUAAAUGAGACUUGUUUUCCCCUCUCUUUGAGUCAAGUCAAAUAUGUAGAUUGCCUUUGGCAAUUCUUCUUCUCAAGCACUGACACUCAUUACCGUCUGUGAUUGCCAUUUCUUCCCAAGGCCAGUCUGAACCUGAGGUUGCUUUAUCCUAAAAGUUUUAACCUCAGGUUCCAAAUUCAGUAAAUUUUGGAAACAGUACAGCUAUUUCUCAUCAAUUCUCUAUCAUGUUGAAGUCAAAUUUGGAUUUUCCACCAAAUUCUGAAUUUGUAGACAUACUUGUACGCUCACUUGCCCCAGAUGCCUCCUCUGUCCUCAUUCUUCUCUCCCACACAAGCAGUCUUUUUCUACAGCCAGUAAGGCAGCUCUGUCGUGGUAGCAGAUGGUCCCAUUAUUCUAGGGUCUUACUCUUUGUAUGAUGAAAAGAAUGUGUUAUGAAUCGGUGCUGUCAGCCCUGCUGUCAGACCUUCUUCCACAGCAAAUGAGAUGUAUGCCCAAAGACGGUAGAAUUAAAGAAGAGUAAAAUGGCUGUUGAAGCACUUUCUGUCCUGGUAUUUUGUUUUUGCUUUUGCCACACAGUAGCUCAGAAUUUGAACAAAUAGCCAAAAGCUGGUGGUUGAUGAAUUAUGAACUAGUUGUAUCAACACAAAGCAAGAGUUGGGGAAAGCCAUAUUUAACUUGGUGAGCUGUGGGAGAACCUGGUGGCAGAAGGAGAACCAACUGCCAAGGGGAAAGAGAAGGGGCCUCCAGCAGCGAAGGGGAUACAGUGAGCUAAUGAUGUCAAGGAGGAGUUUCAGGUUAUUCUCGUCAGCUCCACAAAUGGGUGCUUUGUGGUCUCUGCCCGCGUUACCUUUCCUCUCAAUGUACCUUUGUGUGAACUGGGCAGUGGAGGUGCCUGCUGCAGUUACCAUGGAGUUCAGGCUCUGGGCAGCUCAGUCAGGCAAAACACACAAACAGCCAUCAGCCUGUGUGGGCUCAGGGCACCUCUGGACAAAGGCUUGUGGGGCAUAACCUUCUUUACCACAGAGAGCCCUUAGCUAUGCUGAUCAGACCGUAAGCGUUUAUGAGAAACUUAGUUUCCUCCUGUGGCUGAGGAGGGGCCAGCUUUUUCUUCUUUUGCCUGCUGUUUUCUCUCCCAAUCUAUGAUAUGAUAUGACCUGGUUUGGGGCUGUCUUUGGUGUUUAGAAUAUUUGUUUUCUGUCCCAGGAUAUUUCUUAUAAGAACCUAACUUCAAGAGUAGUGUGCGAGUACUGAUCUGAAUUUAAAUUAAAAUUGGCUUAUAUUAGGCAGUCACAGACAGGAAAAAUAAGAGCUAUGCAAAGAAAGGGGGAUUUAAAGUAGUAGGUUCUAUCAUCUCAAUUCAUUUUUUUCCAUGAAAUCCCUUCUUCCAAGAUUCAUUCCCUCUCUCAGACAUGUGCUAGCAUGGGUAUUAUCAUUGAGAAAGCACAGCUACAGCAAAGCCACCUGAAUAGCAAUUUGUGAUUGGAAGCAUUCUUGAGGGAUCCCUAAUCUAGAGUAAUUUAUUUGUGUAAGGAUCCCAAAUGUGUUGCACCUUUCAUGAUACAUUUCUUCUCUGAAGAGGGUACGUGGGGUGUGUGUAUUUAAAUCCAUCCUAUGUAUUACUGAUUGUCCUGUGUAGAAAGAUGGCAAUUAUUCUGUCUCUUUCUCCAAGUUUGAGCCACAUCUCAGCCACAUUGUUAGACAGUGUACAGAGAACCUAUCUUUCCUUUUUUUUUUUUUAAAGGACAGGAUUUUGCUGUGUUGCCCAGGCUAGACUUGAACUCCUGGGCUCAAGUAAUCCACCUCAGCCUGAGUAGCUGAGACUACAGCCCAUCUUAUUUCUUUAAAUCAUUCAUCUCAGGCAGAGAACUUUUCCCUCAAACAUUCUUUUUAGAAUUAGUUCAGUCAUUCCUAAAACAUCCAAAUGCUAGUCUUCCACCAUGAAAAAUAGAUUGUCACUGGAAAGAACAGUAGCAAUUUCCAUAAGGAUGUGCCUUCACUCACACGGGACAGGCGGUGGUUAUAGAGUCGGGCAAAACCAGCAGUAGAGUAUGACCAGCCAAGCCAAUCUGCUUAAUAAAAAGAUGGAAGACAGUAAGGAAGGAAAGUAGCCACUAAGAGUCUGAGUCUGACUGGGCUACAGAAUAAAGGGUAUUUAUGGACAGAAUGUCAUUACAUGCCUAUGGGAAUACCAAUCAUAUUUGGAAGAUUUGCAGAUUUUUUUUCAGAGAGGAAAGACUCACCUUCCUGUUUUUGGUUCUCAGUAGGUUCGUGUGUGUUCCUAGAAUCACAGCUCUGACUCCAAAUGACUCAAUUUCUCAAUUAGAAAAAGUAGAAGCUUUCUAAGCAACUUGGAAGAAAACAGUCAUAAGUAAGCAAUUUGUUGAUUUUACUACAGAAGCAACAACUGAAGAGGCAGUGUUUUUACUUUCAGACUCCGGGAUUCCCAUUCUGUAGUCUCUCUGCUUUUAAAAACCCUCCUUUUGCAAUAGAUGCCCAAACAGAUGAUGUUUAUUACUUGUUAUUUACGUGGCCUCAGACAGUGUAUGUAUUCUCGAUAUAACUUGUAGAGUGUGAAAUAUAAGUUUAACUACCAAAUAAGGUCUCCCAGGGUUAGAUGACUGCGGGAAGCCUUUGAUCCCAACCCCCAAGGCUUUGUAUAUUUGAUCAUUUGUGAUCUAACCCUGGAAGAAAAAGAGCUCAGAAACCACUAUGAAAAAAUUUGUUCAGUGUUUUCUGUGUUCCCGUAGGUUCUGGAGUCUGAGGAUGCAAAGAUGAAUAAGAUAAAUUCUCAGAAUGUAGUUAUAAUCUCUUGUUUUCUGGUAUAUGCCAUCUUUCUUUAACUUCUCUAAAAUAUUGGGUAUUUGUCAAAUAACCACUUUUAACAGUUACCAUUACUGAGGGCUUAUACAUUGGUGUUAUAAAAGUGACUUGAUUCAGAAAUCAAUCCAUUCAGUAAAGUACUCCUUCUCUAAAUUUGCUGUUAUGUCUAUAAGGAACAGUUUGACCUGCCCUUCUCCUCACCUCCUCACCUGCCUUCCAACAUUGAAUUUGGAAGGAGACGUGAAAAUUGGACAUUUGGUUUUGCCCUUGGGCUGGAAACUAUCAUAUAAUCAUAAGUUUGAGCCUAGAAGUGAUCCUUGUGAUCUUCUCACCUCUUUAAAUUCCCACAACACAAGAGAUUAAAAACAGAGGUUUCAGCUCUUCAUAGUGCGUUGUGAAAUGGCUGGCCAGAGUGUACCAACAAAGCUGUCAUCGGGCUCACAGCUCAGAGACAUCUGCAUGUGAUCAUCUGCAUAGUCCUCUCCUCUAACGGGAAACACCUCAGAUUUGCAUAUAAAAAAGCACCCUGGUGCUGAAAUGAACCCCUUUCUUGAACAUCAAAGCUGUCUCCCACAGCCUUGGGCAGCAGGGUGCCUCUUAGUGGAUGUGCUGGGUCCACCCUGAGCCCUGACAUGUGGUGGCAGCAUUGCCAGUUGGUCUGUGUGUCUGUGUAGCAGGGACGAUUUCCCAGAAAGCAAUUUUCCUUUUGAAAUACGUAAUUGUUGAGACUAGGCAGUUUCAAAGUCAGCUGCAUAUAGUAGCAAGUACAGGACUGUCUUGUUUUUGGUGUCCUUGGAGGUGCUGGGGUGAGGGUUUCAGUGGGAUCAUUUACUCUCACAUGUUGUCUGCCUUCUGCUUCUGUGGACACUGCUUUGUACUUAAUUCAGACAGACUGUGAAUACACCUUUUUUAUAAAUACCUUUCAAAUUCUUGGUAAGAUAUAAUUUUGAUAGCUGAUUGCAGAUUUUCUGUAUUUGUCAGAUUAAUAAAGACUGCAUGAAUCCA